GCCGCCCAGGACCCGCAGCAGAGACGACGCCUGCAGCAAGGAGACCAGGAAGGGGUGAGACAAGGAAGAGCCCCUAGGAUGUCUGAGCUGGAGAAGGCCAUGGUGGCCCUCAUCGACGUUUUCCACCAAUAUUCUGGAAGGGAGGGAGACAAGCACAAGCUGAAGAAAUCCGAACUGAAGGAGCUCAUCAACAAUGAGCUUUCCCAUUUCUUAGAGGAAAUCAAAGAGCAGGAGGUUGUGGACAAAGUCAUGGAAACACUGGACAAUGAUGGAGACGGCGAAUGUGACUUCCAGGAAUUCAUGGCCUUUGUUGCCAUGGUUACUACUGCCUGCCACGAGUUCUUUGAACAUGAGUGAGAUUAGAAAGCAGCCAAACCUUUCCUGUAACAGAGACGGUCAUGCAAGAAAGCAGACAGCAAGGGCUUGCAGCCUAGUAGGAGCUGAGCUUUCCAGCCGUGUUGUAGCUAAUUAGGAAGCUUGAUUUGCUUUGUGAUUGAAAAAUUGAAAACCUCUUUCCAAAGGCUGUUUUAACGGCCUGCAUCAUUCUUUCUGCUAUAUUAGGCCUGUGUGUAAGCUGACUGGCCCCAGGGACUCUUGUUAACAGUAACUUAGGAGUCAGGUCUCAGUGAUAAAGCGUGCACCGUGCAGCCCGCCAUGGCCGUGUAGACCCUAACCCGGAGGGAACCCUGACUACAGAAAUUACCCCGGGGCACCCUUAAAACUUCCACUACCUUUAAAAAACAAAGCCUUAUCCAGCAUUAUUUGAAAACACUGCUGUUCUUUAAAUGCGUUCCUCAUCCAUGCAGAUAACAGCUGGUUGGCCGGUGUGGCCCUGCAAGGGCGUGGUGGCUUCGGCCUGCUUCCCGGGAUGCGCCUGAUCACCAGGUGAACGCUCAGCGCUGGCAGCGCUCCUGGAAAAAGCAACUCCAUCAGAACUCGCAAUCCGAGCCAGCUCUGGGGGCUCCAGCGUGGCCUCCGUGACCCAUGCGAUUCAAGUCGCGGCUGCAGGAUCCUUGCCUCCAACGUGCCUCCAGCACAUGCGGCUUCCGAGGGCACUACCGGGGGCUCUGAGCCACCGCGAGGGCCUGCGUUCAAUAAAAAGAGCGCAGCUUGGGA